GCCAUUGGCCCUUCGCCCACCCGGGAGCUGUGAUCCUGCACUUCGGGUCCCUGAGGUCUGGAUUCUUUCUCCCCUACUGAGACGCAGCCAGUAGGUCCACAGGCCGAUCCAACUGGGAGUUGAAGUGGGUCAGGACGAAGGAAGAAGGAGGGCUUCGGAGUGCGACGGGGGUUAGGUGAAGCUGGGGCAAUGCUGGGGUGCUGUUGGUGGUAUUCCAGUCCCAGAAACGCCUGGAACUCCCAACAGAGGACAAAUUCCAGACUCCUCAAGGGACAUCAAGGCUGGAAUGUCGUGGACGACUGAAAUAUGAGUUGGCGAGGAAGAAGAUAUAGACCAAGACGAUGUUUACGACUUGCUCAGCUGGUUGGGCCUAUGCUUGAGCCCAGUGUGCCAGAGCCUCAACAAGAAGAACCACCAACUGAAAGUCAGGAUCAUACACCUGGUCAGAAGAGAGAAGAUGAUCAGGGUGCAGCUGAGAUUCAAGUGCCUAACCUGGAAGCUGAUCUCCAGGAGCUGUCUCAGUCAAAGACUGGGGAUGAAUGCGGAGAUAGUCCUGAUGUCCAGGGGAAGAUUCUGCCAAAAUCAGAGCAAUUUAAAAUGCCAGAAGGAGGGGAAGGGAAACCACAGCUUUAAACGAAGACAACCAAAAGAAUGCAAACUGGAUUUAUCCGAGAUAUUUGACUUUUAAAAAUCUCAAUAAAGUUUUCCAGUUUUCUCCAAA